AGUUCUGUGGAGCAGCGGUGGCCGGCUAGGAUGGGCUGUCUCUGGGGUCUGGCUCUGCCCCUUUUCUUCUUCUGCUGGGAGGUUGGGGUCUCUGGGAGCUCUGCAGGCCCCAGCACCCGCAGAGCAGACACUGCGAUGACAACGGACGACACAGAAGUGCCCGCUAUGACUCUAGCACCGGGCCACGCCGCUCUGGAAACUCAAACGCUGAGCGCUGAGACCUCUUCUAGGGCCUCAACCCCAGCCGGCCCCAUUCCAGAAGCAGAGACCAGGGGAGCCAAGAGAAUUUCCCCUGCAAGAGAGACCAGGAGUUUCACAAAAACAUCUCCCAACUUCAUGGUGCUGAUCGCCACCUCCGUGGAGACAUCAGCCGCCAGUGGCAGCCCCGAGGGAGCUGGAAUGACCACAGUUCAGACCAUCACAGGCAGUGAUCCCAGGGAAGCCAUCUUUGACACCCUUUGCACCGAUGACAGCUCUGAAGAGGCAAAGACACUCACAAUGGACAUAUUGACAUUGGCUCACACCUCCACAGAAGCUAAGGGCCUGUCCUCAGAGAGCAGCGCCUCUUCCGACAGCCCCCAUCCAGUCAUCACCCCGUCACGGGCCUCAGAGAGCAGCGCCUCUUCCGACGGCCCCCAUCCAGUCAUCACCCCGUCACGGGCCUCAGAGAGCAGCGCCUCUUCCGACGGCCCCCAUCCAGUCAUCACCCCGUCACGGGCCUCAGAGAGCAGCGCCUCUUCCGACGGCCCCCAUCCAGUCAUCACCCCGUCACGGGCCUCAGAGAGCAGCGCCUCUUCCGACGGCCCCCAUCCAGUCAUCACCCCGUCACGGGCCUCAGAGAGCAGCGCCUCUUCCGACGGCCCCCAUCCAGUCAUCACCCCGUCACGGGCCUCAGAGAGCAGCGCCUCUUCCGACGGCCCCCAUCCAGUCAUCACCCCGUCACGGGCCUCAGAGAGCAGCGCCUCUUCCGACGGCCCCCAUCCAGUCAUCACCCCGUCACGGGCCUCAGAGAGCAGCGCCUCUUCCGACGGCCCCCAUCCAGUCAUCACCCCGUCACGGGCCUCAGAGAGCAGCGCCUCUUCCGACGGCCUCCAUCCAGUCAUCACCCCGUCACGGGCCUCAGAGAGCAGCGCCUCUUCCGACGGCCCCCAUCCAGUCAUCACCCCGUCACGGGCCUCAGAGAGCAGCGCCUCUUCCGACGGCCCCCAUCCAGUCAUCACCCCCUCAUGGUCCCCGGGAUCUGACGUCACUCUCCUCGCUGAAGCCCUGGUGACUGUCACAAACAUCGAGGUUAUUAAUUGCAGCAUCACAGAAAUAGAAACAACGACUUCCAGCAUCCCUGGGGCCUCAGACACAGAUCUCAUCCCCACGGAAGGGGUGAAGGCCUCGUCCACCUCCGAUCCACCAGCUCUGCCUGACUCCACUGAAGCAAAACCACACAUCACUGAGGUCACAGCCUCUGCCGAGACCCUGUCCACAGCCGGCACCACAGAGUCAGCUGCACCUGAUGCCACGGUUGGGACCCCACUCCCCACUAACAGCGCCACAGAAAGAGAAGUGACAGCACCCGGGGCCACGACCCUCAGUGGAGCUCUGGUCACAGUUAGCAGGAAUCCCCUUGAAGAAACCUCAGCCCUCUCUGUUGAGACACCAAGUUACGUCAAAGUCUCAGGAGCAGCUCCGGUCUCCAUAGAGGCUGGGUCAGCAGUGGGCAAAACAACUUCCUUUGCUGGGAGCUCUGCUUCCUCCUACAGCCCCUCGGAAGCCGCCCUCAAGAACUUCACCCCUUCAGAGACACCGACCAUGGACAUCGCAACCAAGGGGCCCUUCCCCACCAGCAGGGACCCUCUUCCUUCUGUCCCUCCGACUACAACCAACAGCAGCCGAGGGACGAACAGCACCUUAGCCAAGAUCACAACCUCAGCGAAGACCACGAUGAAGCCCCCAACAGCCACGCCCACGACUGCCCGGACGAGGCCGACCACAGACGUGAGUGCAGGUGAAAAUGGAGGUUUCCUCCUCCUGCGGCUGAGUGUGGCUUCCCCGGAAGACCUCACUGACCCCAGAGUGGCAGAAAGGCUGAUGCAGCAGCUCCACCGGGAACUCCACGCCCACGCGCCUCACUUCCAGGUCUCCUUACUGCGUGUCAGGAGAGGCUAACGGACAUCAGCUGCAGCCAGGCAUGUCCCGUAUGCCAAAAGAGGGUGCUGCCCCUAGCCUGGGCCCCCACCGACAGACUGCAGCUGCGUUACUGUGCUGAGAGGUACCCAGAAGGUUCCCAUGAAGGGCAGCAUGUCCAAGCCCCUGACCCCAGAUGUGGCAACAGGACCCUCGCUCACAUCCACCGGAGUGUAUGUGUGGGGAGGGGCUUCACCUGUUCCCAGAGGUGUCCUUGGACUCACCUUGGCACAUGUUCUGUGUUUCAGUAAAGAGAGACCUGAUCACCCAUCUGUGUGCUUCCAUCCUGCAUUAAAAUUCACUCAGUGUGGCCCA